GACCUUCUGUUCUCGCCGGUCUCCGUGCGGCGGCAUCUCCGUGUCCCUGUGACUCGAGACCGCGGCUGUCGGGUCUCCCCCUCUCUGACCCUGCGUCUCUGUCCCCGCUGUGUCCGCCCUCUCUCCGUGACUCUGUGUGUCUCUCGCUGUCUUGCUGUGGCUGUCACUCCCAGGCUGUCUCCCAGUGAGUCCUGCUCUCCGUCUGCAUGUGUCCCUCUCCCUUGUCGCUGACUCCUCGGCUCUCUCCGGGGCUGUUUCUCCAUCCUGUCCCGCCUCUGCCUGUCAUUGCCUUUCUGCCUCCCCAGCCCCAGAAUUUCCAUCCCUGCACCCUGCAAGUCUACCUCUCUCCUCUCCUCUCCUCCUAAGACCUGCCUUCCUCCUCUCCCCUCUCAUACCCAAGCUGGCCUCCCUUGGUUCCCUCGGUACUUCCUGGACUCUACCUCGGAAACUUCAUUGAUGCCAAAGACCUGGAUCAGCUGGGCCGAAAUAAGAUCACACACAUCAUCUCUAUCCAUGAGUCACCCCAGCCUCUGCUGCAGGAUAUCACCUACCUUCGCAUCCCGGUCGCUGAUACCCCUGAGGUACCCAUCAAAAAGCACUUCAAAGAAUGUAUCAACUUCAUCCACUGCUGCCGCCUUAAUGGGGGGAACUGCCUUGUGCACUGCUUUGCAGGCAUCUCUCGCAGCACCACGAUUGUGACAGCGUAUGUGAUGACUGUGACGGGGCUAGGCUGGCGGGACGUGCUUGAAGCCAUCAAGGCCACCAGGCCCAUCGCCAACCCCAACCCAGGCUUUAGGCAGCAGCUUGAAGAGUUUGGCUGGGCCAGUUCCCAGAAGGAUGGCUCCGGAUUUGCCACAGAGGAUGAGGACAAGGAGUGGCCCCACAGGCUGGCCCAGCAGGGUUCCUUACUACCACCCAUCCUCCUCCAGGCCCUUUGGUUGACCACAGGUGCCAGACAUAGGACCUCAAAAACCUCUGGUGCCCAAUGCCCUCCGAUGACUUCAGCAACCUGCCUGCUGGCUGCACGUGUGGCUCUUCUCUCCGCAGCGCUGGUGCGCGAAGCCACCGGGCGCACAGCCCAGCGCUGUCGUCUGAGUCCGCGGGCGGCCGCCGAGCGCCUGCUGGGGCCGCCACCUCACGUUGCAGCAGGAUGGUCACCGGACCCAAAGUACCAGAUCUGUCUGUGCUUCGGUGAGGAGGACCCGGGCCCCACACAGCACCCCAAGGAGCAGCUCAUCAUGGCGGACGUGCAGGUGCAGCUUCGGCCUGGGAGCUCGUCCUGCACUCUAAGUGCCUCAACCGAGCGCCCAGAUGGGUCCUCAACCCCUGGCAACCCCGAUGGCAUCACUCACCUUCAAUGCAGCUGCCUCCAUCCUAAGCGAGCCGCUUCCUCUUCUUGUACCCGCUGAAGGCAGCCCCCAACAGGGGGGCUCCCUACUCCCACCCAACCCUGCCCACACUAAGCCCAUAGACUUGGGGCCUCCCCCGGCACAUCACCCAGGUCUGCCGGACGGCAGAGGUGGAUCGCGGCCUUCCACUCCUCUGUCACGGGGCCCCGGAACUCGAGAGUAGGCCACACCGCCCCCCAGCUGGGCAUGGGGCUUCGGCAGGAAACUGAACUUGAUCUUGAGGCCCCAGAAAGGCAGCAACUGGAGCAGAAGCAAGACUUCAUCUCUUGCUGACAGCCCAAUUUGUCAAUAGCGCUUUCCUCAGAGCCAGCCUUAACCUGCUGUUGAGUCCAUUAAAACGUUUGCUUAAAGUUUUUACCAAUAAUUAGAUCAUCAGGGUUGUUUAGUGUGGGAUCAAGCCAUAACAAAACUGCCUAGCCUCUCAGGGGCCUAGAAUUUACAGAACCUUCCUCCUCCCUGCAGCUAGUCUCUCUUCUUUAUUCUGGGGGCUGGGAAGGAUCCCAAAACAGGGAACUUGGCCGAACCCUGGGCUUUGGAUGCUAACCACUGAAGUACCAGCACCUGUAGGAUGCUGUCUUUGAAGAAACUGAGGCGGACCUCCAAAUGCAGCCCUAAGGCAGAGGUCAACGUGGAAGACCAGCCCUUCUCCAAGCCCCACUGGUCUUUGCAAGCUGUACGUUGUAGGCAAUCUGAGAACUGGAAAGGGGGACUACAACCAGAAAGUUGGUUACCCUGCCAUGGGAAUAAAGUAGCUGUUUUCCACCCCA